CUUCCGCCGUCCGCCGGUGGCGAGGCCCAGGCUGUCGCCGGGUGUGCAGCGGCGUCGCGGCCAGUAGAGGGAUUCUGGGUAACGGCCCGGACCCCCGGCUGGGCUUCUGGCUCGGCGCAGCAGGUUCCAUUCACGCCAAGUCUGUUGGCAGUGGCAGUUGUAGGGCCAAGGGCGGUUGUAGGACCCGGAGCAGCCGGACAUGGAACAACCGUGGCCGCCUCCGGGACCCUGGAGCCUCCCUCGGGCCGAGGGUGAGGCUGAGGAAGAGAGUGACUUCGACGUGUUCCCCAGUUCUCCCCGCUGCCCGCAGCUGCCAGGCGGCGGCGCCCAGAUGUAUAGCCAUGGAAUUGAAUUGGCUUGCCAAAAGCAGAAAGAGUUUGUGAAGAGCUCUGUGGCGUGCAAAUGGAAUCUUGCUGAAGCUCAACAGAAACUUGGUAGCUUAGCACUGCAUAAUUCUGAGUCCUUGGAUCAGGAGCAUGCCAAAGCACAAACAGCAGUAUCAGAACUGAGGCAACGGGAAGAAGAGUGGCGACAGAAAGAAGAAGCUCUAGUACAAAGAGAGAAGAUGUGUCUGUGGAGCACGGAUGCCAUUAGCAAGGAUGUUUUUAAUAAGAGUUUUAUUAAUCAAGAUAAAAGAAAAGACACAGAAGAUGAAGAUAAAUCAGAAUCAUUUAUGCAAAAAUAUGAGCAAAAAAUCAGACAUUUUGAUAUAUCUUAACAAGAGACCUGGAAUACCUGCAAUUUCUGCUUUACCAAGUUCCAUCAGUGGAGAGUGGACCAACUUGUAGUCAUGGGGAAUGAUGAGAUAAUAAUCCCUGUGGACUGAAUUAUGGCACAGAGUUGAUAGAGGUGUGACACAAGACAGUGAAAAUUUGUGGCUAUGCCUGCUUGAUGGAAGAUUUCUGUUGUAUGCUUAUUGUGAUGAAAGAAGAAAGCUUACCAAAAUGAUGACUAUAUUGGUAUACUCCUUUAUUUUGUUUUUUUGUUGUUGUUUAACUUUUGUUUUAAAUUCAGGGGUACAUGUGCAGGAUGUGCAGGUUUGUUACAUAGGUAAGCGUGUGUCUUGGGGAUUUGUUGUACAGAUUAUUACAUCACCCAGGUAUUAAGCCUAGUAUUCAUUAGUUAUUUUUCCUGAUCCUCCCACCCUCCGCCCUUCGGUAAACUCCAGUGUGUGUUGUUCCCCUUUAUGUGUGCAUGUAUUCUCAUCAUUUAGCUCCCGCUUAUAGGUGAGAAUAUGCGGUAUUUGGUUUUCUGUUCCUUUGUUAGUUUGCUUAGGAUAAUGGCUUCUGGUAUACUCUUCUAAACACAUCUGCAAUAGGAGAUGUAAUUAAAGCUUCCAGUUGGAGGCUUUCUGGACUUGGAUUGCAUUCUGGACUCUUGGUUGACACGGGCCUGGUGUGUGUGGGGGCUGUAUAGGGCUAUAGGGGCUUUACACCCAUGUUUCUCUGUGGUCUUAUUUGUACUUAUAUUCUUCAGAGUUUUUCCUAACUUUUCCCUUAUACAAUUUGUUGACUGCCUUUCUUGUGCUGCUUUUACCCUUACAAUUAGGUGGAAUUUACCACCUAGUGGUAAAUGGUACAAUAUAUCAUGGACUAUUAUAAAGCAUUGAAAUCUGACUUUUUCCUCUACAUUUGUAUUUAGUUUAUUAAUUUAGUUAAUUCACGUUUUAUAAAUAUAAAAUAUUAAUUUAAAAACAAAGGCUUUUAUCUCUUAAAUUUCACAACCGUUAUAUUCACAGUUAUAUGCAUGUUUGACAUCACUGGCUUUAUGGUCAUCAGAGCUGCUUUUUGAGUCAUCUAAUUUUCAGAGCACAUCAUCUUCACUUUCAGCCAAAGUUAGCUGUGAUUCAGCUUUUUUUAAUCUGUGUAGGAUGUUGUCACUGGAAAUUUUACCAAGAGCUAUAAAAGUUUGCUCAAAUACUAUGAUAGAAGUUUUUUCGUUUGUUCUGACUAUGAAUAUUUACAACCUCUUCAAUGUAAUUGUUCAUUGCUUUUAAAAAACAUAUCAAUAUCUUAUUUUUGAAAAACAUUUAAUAUAAAGCACUCUUACAUAUGAAGUGAAAUGAAUAGAAAAUGUAUAUGAUUUUAAUGUUUUUUUUUUUUUUGAGACGAAAUCUCGCUCUUGUCCCCCAGGCUGGAGUACAGUGGUGUGAUCUCAGCUCACUGCAACCUCCGCCUCCCGGGUUCAAGCGUUCCUGCUGCCUCAGCCUCCCGAGUAGCUGGGAUUACAGGCGCCUGCUACCACGCCUGGCUAAUUUUUGUAUUUUUAGUAGAGAUGGGGUUUCACCAUGUUGGCCAGGCUGGCCUUGAACUCCUGACCUCAAAUGAUCCGCCCGCCUCGGCCUCUCAAAGUGCUGGGAUUACAGGCGUGAGCCACCACUCUGAGCCUUAAUUUUGGUUUUUUAAAAAGUCAUUCAAAAAUAUGCCUGGAAGGAAAUACAUCAAAAUGUUAACAGUAAUCUCUUGUGGUAGAAUUACAGCUAACUUUUAUUUUCCGGAUUUUAAAAAUUCUUCAUAAUAAAUAAACUUUAUUUUUAUAAUCUGAAAAAAAUUUUUCAAAGCGUUUAUCCUAAGAAUCAAAAUGGCUUAACAUUAGAAAACUCAUUAAUGUGAUUCACUGUAUUAACUGAUCAUAGUAGUAUAACCACAGGACUUGGUGGUCAAUUUGAUGUGGGAGAAAUGGAAAUGUCAGAGGAAUUUCUAGAAUGCUUGAUUUGGUAACAUGGAGCCUAGGAAACAUUGUAGGAUGGCAGAGAGACAAGUAUGGGUUUGGUUUCAAGUAAGAUGGGUUUACGUGCAGGCAUAUCAGUAGAAAUGCAUAUGGUGGUAGACGAUUGGAAAUAGAGGAGAUCUGGAGUUUAGGAAUAUGGGAAAUGAUCAUACAACUUUCCUCAAGUAAUUCACAAACUACCUGGGAGAUUUUUAGUACACAGAGAAAUUAAAAUGAAUUAGUGUAGUUUGUUAAAAUAUAUCAUUCUAAGCCUGGCAUAGUGGUUCUGCCUGUAAUCCCAGCACUUUGAGAAACUGAGGCUGGAGGAUCACUUGAGCCCAGGGAUUCAAGACCAGCCUGGGCAACACAGUGAAACCUCAUCUCUACAAAAAAAAAAAAAAAUUCGUCAGGUGUGGAGGCUUAUACCUGUAGUCCCAGCUACUGCAGAGGCUGAGGUGGGAGGAUCUCUUGAGCCCAGGAGGUUGAGGCUGCAAUGAGUUGUGAUUGCACCAGUGUACUCUAGCCUAGACAACAGAGGAAUAACCUGUCUCUCAAGAUAAAGAAAUAAAUUAAUUAAUAAUAAUAAUAAUUCUAUAAGUGUAAUGAAAGAGGAAAGGGAAAUCAGUAAUAAGGAAGGACGUGUAUUUCAGGACCAUUUUAGGAAUCAGGUGGCAUAUUGAAGGUUGAUGAUGGAUUGAGAUUUAGACGUUCACUAGGGAAAUAUAUAGGUUAAAGCAUAUGAUUAAAAUAUCUAAACUUGUCAAAGUGAGGUUUUCCAAGCAUUCAGAGAAAUUGUUUGGCUAGUUUAAAUGACUGUAUUAUCCUUAACCAAAGGAUUAGCUAAAUAAACAUUUUGAAUGGGUGCUUAUCAUUUAUCGAGUAUUUACUAUGUCUCAGGCACUGUUCUAAGUGCUUUAUAUGAAUUAAUAGCAUUUAAUUGUCAUGAAAAUCCUGAGUUAGGUACUAUUUUUAGCCCUAUUUUACAGAGGAGGAAAUGGAGGCAUAUAAAGGGAACUGCAGUAGUAAAAUGGUGAAGCCAGUAUUUGAACCUGGGCCAUUUAGCUCUAGUCUGUCUUCUCAGCCGCUGUCUUAAAUUGUUACUCUCCAUUUGUAUACAAGUUUGUUUACAAAUUCCAAAAUAAUAUCAGUAAUUUGAGGUAUAUGCUGUUCCACUGAGUUGUUGAUUCUCCUUAUGUGUUUUAUUUUUGAAACAGAGUCAUUUUCUGUCACCCAGGCUGGAUUACAGUCACAAGAUCAUAGCAACUGCAGCCUCAAUUUCCUAAGCUCAAGCAAUCCUCUUGCCCCAGCCUUCCAAGUAGCUGGGACUACAAGUGUACUCCGCCAUGCCUGGCUAAUUAUCUCAUUUUGUGUGGAGACACGGUCUCAUUUUGUUGCCUAGACUGACCUAAAACUCCUGUGCUCAGGUGAUUCUCCUGCCUUGGCCUCCCAAAAUGCUGGGAUUACAGGUGUGAGCUACUGCGCCCCACCUGUCUUUAUUUUGUUCAUAAAAUUCCACACUCUUUCCACAAAGGUCUGUAUCGACUACCUGUAACUGAACUUCUCAAUUUCAUACUAAUUCAAUGUGCAUUUUUGAAAUCAAGUGAUAGUAUUUCUCAGAUUUAAAAAAAAAAUGUAUUUUCAAUGUCAAGUGUUAAUUCGUCUCAGGUAUUAAAUAGGUAGUUAAAAAAUAUUAACAUUUGGCAGGGAGUGGUGGCUCACACCUGCAAUCCCAGCACUUUGGGAGGCCGAGGCAGGUGGAUCAUGAGGUUAGGAGUUCGAGACCAGCCUGAUCAACAUGGUGAAACCUUGUCUCUACUAAAAAUACAAAAAUUAACUGGGCGUGGUGACACACGCCUGUAAUCCCAGCUUCCAGGAGGCUGAGGCAGGAGAAUUACUUGAACCCAGGAGGUGGAGGUUGCAGUGAGCUGAGAUCGUGUUGCUGUACUCCAGCCUGGGCAACAGAGUGAGACUCCAUCUCAACAAAAAGAAAAAAAAAAUUAACAUUUAAUGAUACCCUUCCCCAUGGCCCCAAGUGUCAGGAACCCUUUCAUGUUAUCCUUCCUGCAAAAUAAACCAGAAUGGAUAAGGCUUUUGGUAUUUCAGUAAGUCACAAUGCUGCCAUGAAGAAGUAAACAAGAGGAGCAAUGCUUUAUCGUGGAUGGUAGAUAGAGUUGAAAAUAUUACCUCUCCAGAAGUGUAAGAAAGCUAAGGCAAAACUGCUUCAUAGGAUUUACUUUGUGGGUUCAAGUAUAAGAAAUAAGGAUUGUGCUUUCUUUAAAUCUGAGUCCCAGGAAUCAUUAGGCUUUUUUAAGAGAUAUGGUCUUGCUCUGUCACCCAGGCUGAAGUGCAGUGGUGAGGUCAUAGCUCACUGCAGCCUCCACCAUCUGGGCUCAAGGUGUGCUCUCACCUCAGCCUCCCAAAUAGUGGGGAUUACACCACGCCUAGCAAUAUUCUUAUACUUUAAGAAGUAGUUUUAAGUAACUUCCAUAAUCAUUCUGUUUCUCAGAACUUCAAAUGACCUAAUCAUUAUGUCCAAAGCGUUGGGGAAAUAACUUUAUAAAGCUUAGAAUACUCUAUGAGAAAAUGCUACAGUCUUUAUCCUUUUUUUUAAUCCUUUUAAGAGAUGAGGUCUCGCUGUAUUGCCCAAGCUGGAGCACAGUGGUUCCAUCAUACCUUCUGCAGCCUCUAGCUCCUAGGCUCCCAAGUGAUCCUGCCCCCUCAGACUCCCAAGUAGCUGGGACUACAGGUGCACACUACCAUGCCCAGCUAAUUUUUAAGCUUUUUCUGUAGAGACAGGGUCUUACUAUGUUGCUGAGGUUGGCCUGCAACUCCUGGACUCCACCAUUCCUCUGGCCUCAGCCUCCAAAAGUGCUGAGAUUACAAGCAUGUGCCACCAUGCCCAGCUUAUCUCCUUUGAGACAGAGUCUCUCGCUCUGUCGCCCAGGCUGGAGUGCUGUGGUGCAAUCUCGGCUCGCUGCAACCUCCGCCUCCUGGGUUCAAGUGAUUCUUGUGCCUCAGCCUUCCAAGUAGCUGGGAUUUACCUGCCACCAUGCCCAACUAAUUUUUAUAUUUUUAGUAGAGACAGGGUUUUACCAUGUUGGCCAGGCUGGUCUCGAACUCCUGACCUCAGGUGAUCCGCCUGCCUUGGCCUCCCAAAGUGCUGGGAUUGCAGGCAUGAGCCACCGUGGCUGGCCCCACCCCCUUUUUUUAAGUGAGGAGAAAAUGAAUCAUUUAUUUUUGAUUGACUCACAUUGUUGCUGUGUAUUCUCAGUAGGACAUUUGUCUUCAGUUUUGUUCUUUCUUGUGUACUGAUGUGGAAUUAAAUAUAUAGGAGUUCAUUUUGCACCUACAGGAAAAGUUUACUGCUAAACUCUUGAGUCAGCUCUACAAAAUUUCCAUGAAUAUCCAGACUUCUUUGCAUGAGUCUAAGGAAUCUAAACCUAACAUUGCUAUAUUGAAUUUAUUCAGUUAGCCAGGCACAGUGGCUCAUGCCCAUAAUCCCAGCACUUUGGGAGGCCUAGCCAGGAGAAUAUCUUGAGGCCAGGAGUUCAAGACCAGCCUGAGCAACAUAAUAAGCCUCUCAUCUUUAUGGAGAAAAAAAAGAAGAGAAAAAAAGAAAAGAAAAAAAUCUAUUCAGUUAUGACUGACUGGACAACAUUAAAAAGUCAACACUUUGCUGGUUCCGUGAUUUCUUGGUGGUAUUGACUUUGACCAAAUUUCCUGCUAAUUUAGAUAAAGGUGUAGAUAUAACUUAAAUAGUAUUUGGAUUUCUUUGACACCUUGAAACAAAAUGACAACCAUUUUCAAAUAUGCUUAACUAAUUUUUAAAAGACUUUGUUUAUAACAGACAUCAUGAGUAAAUGGCUUACAUAACUAACUCUCAAUUUGCCCAAGACUGCGGGCAUUCAUGGAUGUAGGACUUUUUAAUAUUGAACUGGCCACUCUGGCCUGAUUAAUUAUCUGAAAUAAAACUUCCUGUGAAUUUUAGGAGCUAUUUCCAGUCUACUGAGUAUUGCUUUAAAGAGUACUGUCCCUCACUUGCUCUUUUACCAUAAUCUGUUGCUCUGGUAAUAUGAAUUGUCUUUAAAGAGAAUCAUUUAAAAAUACCAUUGAGAGAUUAAUGAAUUAAGAAUGGUUGGUAUUUCUUCCCUUAUGGGAAGAAAGAAAAUAUUUGACACUUAUGGUUCAAUUCUUUUUUUUACAGGUAUGUUGAGUCGAUGGGAUGAUAGCCAGA